ACUUCCGGGAGUCGGAAAGGAAAGCUGUGGGACCAUCCUGGCAACCCCGGUGUUUGGCUGGGUUCUAGCGUAGCCGUCUGUGUGGCCGGUGGGGGACCUGCGGUCGGAGUGGGAGGGCCAGUCUGCACCCAAGAGGUGGAAGAGGACGGGCUUUAGGCUGGAAGCGCCUUAGAGGAGCCAUUUUUCCAGGUGGGGCCCCAGGCAGAGGCUCCGACAGGGAGCCUGGCCAUAGUCGCGCAGCCGGGGAGGUGGAGCGCGUCCCAGACCCGAGCCCCCGACCUCAGCCAAACCCAUUCCUUCUGCCCUUGGAGGCCAGAGGGGACUCUGAGCUCCGGAAAGCAGGAUGCCUGGUUUGCUUUUAUGUGAACCAACAGAGCUUUACAACAUCCUGAAUCAGGCCACAAAACUCUCCAGAUUAACAGACCCCAACUAUCUCUGUUUAUUGGAUGUCCGUUCCAAAUGGGAGUAUGACGAAAGCCAUGUGAUCACUGCCCUUCGAGUGAAGAAGAAAAAUAAUGAAUAUCUUCUCCCGGAGUCUGUGGACCUGGAGUGUGUGAAGUACUGCGUGGUGUAUGAUAACAACAGCAGCACCCUGGAGAUACUCUUAAAAGAUGAUGAUGAUGAUUCAGACUCUGAUGGUGAUGGCAAAGAUCUUGUGCCUCAAGCAGCCAUUGAGUAUGGCAGGAUCCUGACCCGCCUCACCCACCACCCCGUCUACAUCCUGAAAGGGGGCUAUGAGCGCUUCUCAGGCACGUACCACUUUCUCCGGACCCAGAAGAUCAUCUGGAUGCCUCAGGAACUGGAUGCAUUUCAGCCAUACCCCAUUGAAAUCGUGCCAGGGAAGGUCUUCGUUGGCAAUUUCAGUCAAGCCUGUGACCCCAAGAUUCAGAAGGACUUGAAAAUCAAAGCCCAUGUCAAUGUCUCCAUGGAUACAGGGCCCUUUUUUGCAGGCGAUGCUGACAAGCUUCUGCACAUCCGGAUAGAAGAUUCCCCGGAAGCCCAGAUUCUUCCCUUCUUACGCCACAUGUGUCACUUCAUUGAAAUUCACCAUCACCUUGGCUCUGUCAUUCUGAUCUUUUCCACCCAAGGUAUCAGCCGCAGUUGUGCCGCCAUCAUAGCCUACCUCAUGCAUAGUAACGAGCAGACCUUGCAGAGGUCCUGGGCCUAUGUCAAGAAGUGCAAAAACAACAUGUGUCCAAAUCGGGGAUUGGUGAGCCAGCUGCUGGAAUGGGAGAAGACUAUCCUUGGAGAUUCCAUCACAAACAUCAUGGAUCCGCUCUACUGAUCUUCUCCGAGGCCCACCGAAGGGUACUGAAGAGCCUCACCUGGGGGCAUUUUGUGGGUGGAGGGCCAGAGUGUGUAUACCCAGGCUUGUCUGGAAGGAGAAGGCCUUUGCUGCCUGAAAGUCUCA